GACGACGCACCGCGGCGCUGCGAGGGGCUCGGUCCCGGGGCGCGCCGGCGAUUGGCGGGGGAACCGGACCCGGGGGCGCGGCCGCCCGCGGAUUGGCGAGGCACGGCGGGGGCGGGCUCGCGCAUGCUCUUAAGUGGCAGCGGCGGGGACGGGGUCAGUGCCAAGAUGUCGACGGCGGCGGUUCCGGAGCUGAAGCAGAUCAGCCGGGUGGAGGCGAUGCGCCUAGGGCCGGGCUGGAGCCACUCGUGCCACGCCAUGCUGUACGCCGCCAACCCUGGGCAGCUCUUCGGCCGCAUCCCCAUGCGCUUCUCGGUGCUGAUGCAGAUGCGUUUCGACGGGCUGCUGGGCUUCCCCGGGGGCUUCGUGGACCGGCGCUUCUGGUCGCUGGAGGACGGCCUGAACCGGGUGCUGGGCCUGGGCCUGGGCUGCCUGCGCCUCACCGAGGCCGACUACCUGAGCUCGCACCUGACCGAGGGCCCACACCGCGUCGUGGCGCACCUGUACGCGCGGCAGCUGACGCUGGAGCAGCUGCACGCCGUGGAGAUCAGCGCGGUGCACUCGCGCGACCACGGCCUGGAGGUGGGGCCGCCGCCCGGGCCCCGCCCCCCGCCCCGGGGUUUGGCUCUGGCCCCGUGGAAGGCACCGAUGGGUAACACGUCUCCUGAGGGUCCCCUGGCCGGGCUGGGUCGGGUGUCGCUGUCUCCAGCAAUGGGGUGGGGAGAGGGGUCUGGGGCUGGGAGGCCGGGAAAGGAGGGGCGGGGGUGGGGGCCGGCGCUGGGGCUCCCUCAGGGCUGUGUUACAUCCGCCUUGCUGCCUGCCAUUGCCAAUCCUGGGAGUGGGGGAGUGGGAUCGGUGGGGAGGAAGGGAUGGGGGAGGAGCGGGGAUUGCUUGGGGAGUUGGGAAACUUGAGCACAGCGGGGGUUGUAAAACUUGGGAACCUCAUGUUGGGCGUGAAGGCUCUUGGGAUUUGUACUUUGUGGUCUGGAAGGGCUGGACUGCGGGUGUUCAGGCUUCGUUGGGUGGACGGGGGGAGCAUGGGGUGCGGACCCCGGGGUGGGGUGGCCUGGGUACGAGGGGGGGGAGUGCAUGGGGUCAGCCUCCACACUUGCUUGGGGAGGAGGGGGCUGCACUGCUCCGAGGGAGCUGGCUGGCUUCUGCCAGGCCCUGCGUGGGUCUCCCAUUAAGUCCUUGGCAAAGCUGGCUGCUCAUACCCUGGCCUCAUAGCUUCCAGGCCCCUCCUGCUGGAGGUGCCAUUGUGUGGCAGGCCUGGCCCCAACCCCUACCUCCUGUCUGCGCAGGUGCUGGGCCUCGUGCGGGUCCCGCUGUACACCCAGAAGGACCGAGUCGGAGGCUUCCCCAACUUCCUGAGCAACGCCUUCGUGAGCACGGCUAAGUGCCAGCUCCUCUUUGCCCUCAAGGUGCUCAACAUGAUGCCCGAGGAGAAGCUGGUUGAGGCCCUGGCUGCAGCCACCGAGAAGCAGAAGAAGGCCCUGGAGAAGUUGCUCCCGGCCUCCUCUUGAGGGCUGCCUGAGCUGGUGGCACCCUCCCCUGGGCCGGAAGACUGGGAAUUCCUGCUAAGUGUGGCUUCUAGAGUGUUUGUGUGUACCCCGCUUCUGACUGCCUAGGGCGAGUGGGCAUCCUGUCAUCAUCUCCACUGUCCCAAGCAGUCACUAGGUGGCGGCCGGGCCAGCUGGAACCCAGCCCAUCCUCUCAGGCAGAGCAGGGUGGUCCGGGCACACUGGGCCUGCCUCUCCAGCCUCAGGAUGCUCUUGUUUAUUCUGGGCUCAGACCCUCCUCUUGUACGUCUCAUCACAGCUGGUAGAGACCCAGGAGUGCCUGAUUGUCCCACAGGGGUGGCGCACAGCUCUGGGACCACUCAGAAGAUGGGAUGUGUGGGUGGAGGAUGCCUUGUCUCGGUCAGCUCAUUCCUGCCUCCUUCCUGAGCCAGUUCAGGGCCUGGGGGAGAGCCAGCUUGGGGUAGGAAGUUAAUAAUACUGUUAAUUUGGGUUGUUGUUGGAUUUACUUUGCUAGAUUUUCUCUUUCACCACGUGUGAACUGUGGGUGAGGUUUCAAAGUAGCUUCACCCCACGUGGCUUGGUUCCCAGGGACAGUCAGGGCCUCGGGGGCCCAGCUAUGUACAACGAAGCUGUCGAAGGAGAAGACAAUAAAGUCGCUCCGCAGCUGC